UUUUUUUUUUUUUUUUUUUUGAGUCAGAGUCUUGCUCUGUGGCCAGGCUGGAGUGCAAUCUCGACUCACUGCAGCCUCCGGCUCCUGGAUUCAAGUGAGUCUCCUGUCUCAGCCUCCUGAGUAGCUGGAACUACAGGUGCAUGCCACCACACCUGACUAAUUUUUGUAUUUUCAGUAGAGAUGGGGUUUCACCAUGUUGGCCAGGAUGGUCUCGAUCUCUUGACCUUGUGAUCCACCCACCUCGGCCUCCCAAAGUGCUGAGAUUACAGGUGUGAGCCACCACACCCGGCCUACUAUUUCUAUUCUUAUUUUAGCUUCUACCUCACCUCUCUGUGCCCAUGCUGUUCCUCCUGGCUUGGUACCCUGCCCAAGUUGGCAGGUUUUGACUGGGGAGGUGCUUUGGAGCAGGUGCACACAGCCACACCUAGGACAAUUGCUGCUGCUGGACUGGAGCAACAAGGCCACACCAAGCGCAAGUGGAGCACGGGUGACAUCCUGAGAACCUUCAUGGGAGCCUGAGGCAGCCCUACUUAGCAGACCUGUGGUGGCUCUCCUGGAUGAGUAGCCCCAGCCCCUGCCUCUGCUGCUGUGGCAUCACAGAAGCCAUCAGAACCAGCAGAAGCUGCCACCAUGGACACUGUAAAUCACAGAGGCCUUUGAUGAUGCUCAUUCAGAGGACUGAGCAGCAGGACUCUUAGCUGGGGACCAGGAAGGGCAUCUUGGCCUGAAACCAAGAACCACAAUGGCAUUGGCCACUAGUGGCACCUGCCUUCCCCCAUCCCUCUCUCCCAUCCCUACUCCCCACUCAGUCCUGCUCAGUGCCUUCCCACCCCUUGUCUUUUCUCUGGUCAGCUGCGUAGUAAGUGAGAAGGGAGGGGCUACCAGAGGCAGGGAAGGGAGGAGCCUUUGGGUUUAUAAAUUCCAAAAAGGCCACUCAACUCCUAGAGCUGGAUCCUUGAAAAUCUACUCUAUCAGCUGCUGUGGUUGCCACCAUUCUCAGGACCCUCGCCAUGAAAGCCCUUAUGCUGCUCACCCUGUCUGUUCUGCUCUGCUGGGUCUCAGCUGACAUUCGCUGUCACUCCUGCUACAAGGUCCCUGUGCUGGGCUGUGUGGACCGGCAGUCCUGCCGCCUGGAGCCAGGACAGCAAUGCCUGACAACACAUGCAUACCUUGGUAAGAUGUGGGUUUUCUCCAAUCUGCGCUGUGGCACACCAGAAGAGCCCUGUCAGGAGGCCUUCAACCAAACCAACCGCAAGCUGGGUCUGACAUAUAACACCACCUGCUGCAACAAGGACAACUGCAACAGCGCAGGACCCCGGCCCACUCCAGCCCUGGGCCUUGUCUUCCUUACCUCCUUGGCUGGCCUUGGCCUCUGGCUGCUGCACUGAGACUCAUUCCAUUGGCUGCCCCUCCUCCCACCUGCCUUGGCCUGAGCCUCUCUCCCUGUGUCUCUGUAUCCCCUGGCUUUACAGAAUCGUCUCUCCCUAGCUCCCAUUUCUUUAAUUAAACACUGUUCCGAGUGGUCUCCUCAUCCAUCCUUCCCACCUCACACCCUUCACUCUCCUUUUUCUGGGUCCCUUCCCACUUCCUUCCAGGACCUCCAUUGGCUCCUAGAAGGGCUCCCCACUUUGCUUCCUAUACUCUGCUGUCCCCUACUUGAGGAGGGAUUGGGAUCUGGGCCUGAAAUGGGGCUUCUGUGUUGUCCCCAGUGAAGGCUCCCACAAGGACCUGAUGACCUCACUGUACAGAGCUGACUCCCCAAACCCAGGCUCCCAUAUGUACCCCAUCCCCCAUACUCACCUCUUUCCAUUUUGAGUAAUAAAUGUCUGAGUCUGA